AGAGGGCGGAGCGGCGCCGGAGCGGGCGUCAUGGCGCGGCUCCUCUGGUUGCUCCGGGGCCUGACCCUCGGAACUGCGCCUCGGCGGGCGGUGCGGGGCCAAGCGGGCGGCGGCGGGCCCGGCACCGGGCCGGGACUGGGGGAGGCAGGGUCUCUUGCAACGUGUGAGCUGCCUCUUGCCAAGAGUGAGUGGCAAAAGAAACUAACCCCGGAGCAGUUCUACGUCACAAGAGAAAAGGGAACGGAACCGCCUUUCAGUGGGAUCUACCUGAAUAACAAGGAAGCAGGAAUGUAUCAUUGCGUGUGCUGCGACAGUCCACUCUUCAGUUCUGAGAAAAAGUACUGCUCUGGCACUGGGUGGCCUUCGUUUUCCGAGGCUCAUGGUACGUCUGGCUCUGAUGAAAGCCACACAGGGAUCCUGAGACGUCUGGAUACCUCGUUAGGAUCAGCUCGCACAGAGGUUGUCUGCAAGCAGUGUGAAGCUCAUCUAGGUCACGUGUUUCCUGAUGGACCUGGGCCCAAUGGUCAGAGGUUUUGCAUCAACAGUGUGGCUUUGAAGUUCAAACCAAGGAAACACUGACCAUCUUCAAGAGUCCCGUUCCCUUGCCACCCCUUCACGUGCACCCUCAAUUUCCACAAUUCACUUGAAUGACUUGUUUUAUUUGCAAUAAAACUGGGCUGAAUUUGCUGCUGUCUCCAGCGAGUCAUUGCUUCUCUUAAUUUAUUUACCUGGAAUCAACUUAAUCCUGUGUGUUAGGCUGUUCUUGUGUUGCUAUAAAGAAGUACCUGAUCAGGAUCUGGGAGAAUUUGAAAAAAAAAGAAAAACUAGAAAAAUAAACAAAAUUAAAAAGAAAAAAAAAUACCUGAGACUGAGUAACUUAUAAAGAAAAGAGGUUUAAUUGACUCACAGUUCUGCAGGGUGUACAGAAAGCAUGGUGCCAGCAUUUGCUCGGAUUCUGGGGAGACCUGAGGGAGCUUUUACUCAUGGCAGAAGGUGAAGGGGGAGCCGGCGUCUCACAUGGCAAAGCAGGAGCAAGAGAGAGUGGUAGGGAGGUGCCACAUACUUUUAAACAGCCAGAUCUCUCAAGAACUCACUCACUGUCACCAGGACAGCACCAAGCCAUGAGGGAUCCACCCUCAUGACCCAGUUACCUCCCGGCAGGGCCCACCUCCGGCACUAGGAAUUAUACUUCAACAUAAGAUUUGGAGAGGGAAAACAUCCAAACCAUAUCACCCAACUCCCACUUGGAGUAGAACUUCACAAAACGACAGAGGGACAGCUGUUUCCAUCAAACACUUCCACAGCUUCACCUGAGACGAGGGCAUGACUCUGGGAACAUCAGGAGGCUGAUGGACUAUUAAGCCAAACAAUUCCUACAAAAAUUCCCUGCACCUUCCACUGCGUUUCAGUCCUUGACAGACAUAAGUAAGGGAUCAAGUGAGAAGAGGAAGGAAAAUACAGGAUCCAAGGAAUCAACAAUGCUAGCACUGAAGAGCAGGAUUACGGAGGAGCUGUGCUCUGGGAGCAUAUAUGGUGAUCAAUCAGAUGCAUGACUUUUUUUUCAAAAUUUUAAAUGUCUUGAGCAUGCUACUUCCAACCAUUCUACCCACAAAUAAACUGCAAUAGGACUUGGUUAGAUUUCAAUGAUUAUGAAUAAAUGUUCACCUUCAUACCUUCUGGUUACAAAGCUAAACUUUAAAAUGUCCAAAUAAAAUAUUCACUAAAAUUUA